AUACUGAGGCCAGAGUGCCAUCGAAGGUAAUUAUAGAGACAGUAAAAUCCUUUUACUCUGGGAAAAAUAAAAUGCUGGGUGUCUCACAAAAUUUCAGAACCUGAUUUCAAACGGAUCAUAACAAAGAGGAGAUCAAAUUUAGCAUGGUGGACUGCUCGACAGGAUAUAUUUGUCAAUGGAAUGUUUCCACAUAUUAUACCACCAACAUGAGAAAAAAAUGAUCAUUGUUUAUUUGAAGCUUGAUGAUAUUCUAACGCUGCCUUUUCUCUUCUCAUUUUAGAGAAAAAUGAGCAGGCGGAAUUGUUGGAUUUGUAAGAUGUGCAGAGAUGAAUCUAAGAGGCCCCCUUCAAACCUUACUUUGGAGGAAGUAUUACAGUGGGCCCAGUCUUUUGAAAAUUUAAUGGCUACAAAAUAUGGUCCAGUAGUCUAUGCAGCAUAUUUAAAAAUGGAGCACAGUGACGAGAAUAUUCAAUUCUGGAUGGCAUGUGAAACCUAUAAGAAAAUUGCCUCACGGUGGAGCAGAAUUUCUAGGGCAAAGAAGCUUUAUAAGAUUUACAUCCAGCCACAGUCCCCUAGAGAGAUUAACAUUGACAGUUCGACAAGAGAGACUAUCAUCAGGAACAUUCAGGAACCCACUGAAACAUGUUUUGAAGAAGCUCAGAAAAUAGUCUAUAUGCAUAUGGAAAGGGAUUCCUACCCCAGAUUUCUAAAGUCAGAAAUGUACCAAAAACUUUUGAAAACUAUGCAGUCCAACAACAGUUUCUGACUACAACUCAAAAGUUUAAAUAGAAAACAGUAUAUUGAAAGUGGUGGGUUUGAUCUUUUUAUUUAGAAACCCACAAAAUCAGAAACACAGUACAAAUAAAACAGAAAUCAAACUAUAAGUUGACUUUUAGUUCCUAAAAAGAAACAUAUUUCAAAAGCAAUGGAAUCUAGAAUUCUUAUAACAUGAAUAACAAAAUGUACAGCAAGCCUAUGUAGUUCAAUUAAUAUAUAAGGAAAAGGAAGGUCUUUCUUCAUGAUACAAGCAUUAUAAAGUUUUUACUGUAGUAGUCAAUUAAUGGAUAUUUCCUUGUUAAUAAAAUUUUGUGUCAUAAUUUACAAAUUAGUUCUUUAAAAAUUGUUGUUAUAUGAAUUGUGUUUCUAGCAUGAAUGUUCUAUAGAGUACUCUAAAUAACUUGAAUUUAUAGACAAAUGCUACUCACAGUACAAUCAAUUGUAUUAUACCAUGAGAAAAUCAAAAAGGUGUUCUUCAGAGACAUUUUAUCUAUAAAAUUUUCCUACUAUUAUGUUCAUUAACAAACUUCUUUAUCACAUGUAUCUUCUACAUGUAAAACAUUUCUGAUGAUUUUUUAACAAAAAAUAUAUGAAUUUCUUCAUUUGCUCUUGCAUCUACAUUGCUAUAAGGAUAUAAAAUGUGGUUUCUAUAUUUUGAGAUGUUUUUUCCUUACAAUGUGAACUCAUCGUGAUCUUGGAAAUCAAUAAAGUCAAAUAUCAACUAAAGACUUACAUUAUCUUUCUCAAAGACAAAAUAAAUAUAUUUUCCAGUACAAA